CACUAGGAGCGGCUCUCGGUGCAGCGGGACAGGGCGAAGCGGCCUGCGCCCACGGAGCGCGCGACACUGCCCGGAAGGGACCACCACCCUUGCCCCCUCAGCUGCCCACUCGUGAUUUCCAGCGGCCUCCGCGCGCGCACGAUGCCCUCGGCCACCAGCCACAGCGGGAGCGGCAGCAAGUCGUCCGGACCGCCACCGCCGUCGGGUUCCUCCGGGAGUGAGGCGGCCGCGGGAGCCGGGGCCGCCGCGCCGGCUUCUCAGCACCCCGCAACCGGCACCGGCGCUGUCCAGACCGAGGCCAUGAAGCAGAUUCUCGGGGUGAUCGACAAGAAACUUCGGAACCUGGAGAAGAAAAAGGGUAAGCUUGAUGAUUACCAGGAACGAAUGAACAAAGGGGAAAGGCUUAAUCAAGAUCAGCUGGAUGCCGUUUCUAAGUACCAGGAAGUCACAAAUAAUUUGGAGUUUGCAAAAGAAUUACAGAGGAGUUUCAUGGCACUAAGUCAAGAUAUUCAGAAAACAAUAAAGAAGACAGCACGUCGGGAGCAGCUUAUGAGAGAAGAAGCUGAACAGAAACGUUUAAAAACUGUACUUGAGCUACAGUAUGUUUUGGACAAAUUGGGAGAUGAUGAAGUGCGGACUGACCUGAAACAAGGUUUGAAUGGAGUGCCAAUAUUGUCCGAAGAGGAGUUGUCAUUGUUGGAUGAAUUCUAUAAGCUAGUAGACCCUGAACGGGACAUGAGCUUGAGGUUGAAUGAACAGUAUGAACAUGCCUCCAUUCACCUGUGGGACCUGCUGGAAGGGAAGGAAAAACCUGUAUGUGGAACCACCUAUAAAGUUCUAAAGGAAAUUGUUGAGCGUGUUUUUCAGUCAAACUACUUUGACAGCACCCACAACCACCAGAAUGGGCUGUGUGAGGAAGAAGAGGCAGCCUCAGCACCUGCAGUUGAAGACCAGGUACCUGAAGCUGAACCUGAGCCAGCAGAAGAGUACACUGAGCAAAGUGAAGUUGAAUCAACAGAGUAUGUAAAUAGACAGUUCAUGGCAGAAACACAGUUCACCAGUGGUGAAAAGGAGCAGGUAGAUGAGUGGACAGUUGAAACGGUUGAGGUGGUAAAUUCACUCCAGCAGCAACCUCAGGCUGCAUCCCCUUCAGUACCAGAGCCCCACUCUUUGACUCCAGUGGCUCAGGCAGAUCCCCUUGUGAGAAGACAGCGAGUACAAGACCUUAUGGCACAAAUGCAGGGUCCCUAUAAUUUCAUACAGGAUUCAAUGCUGGAUUUUGAAAAUCAGACACUUGAUCCUGCCAUUGUAUCUGCACAGCCUAUGAAUCCAACACAAAACAUGGACAUGCCCCAGCUGGUUUGCCCUCCAGUUCAUUCUGAAUCUAGACUUGCUCAGCCUAAUCAAGUUCCUGUACAACCAGAAGCGACACAGGUUCCUUUGGUAUCAUCCACAAGUGAGGGGUACACAGCAUCUCAACCCUUGUACCAGCCUUCUCAUGCUACAGAGCAACGACCACAGAAGGAACCAAUUGAUCAGAUUCAGGCAACAAUCUCUUUAAAUACAGACCAGACUACAGCAUCAUCAUCCCUUCCUGCUGCGUCUCAGCCUCAAGUAUUUCAGGCUGGGACAAGCAAACCUUUACAUAGCAGUGGAAUCAAUGUAAAUGCAGCUCCAUUCCAAUCCAUGCAAACGGUGUUCAAUAUGAAUGCCCCAGUUCCUCCUGUUAAUGAACCAGAAACUUUAAAACAGCAAAAUCAGUACCAGGCCAGUUAUAACCAGAGCUUUUCUAGUCAGCCUCACCAAGUAGAACAAACAGAGCUUCAGCAAGAACAGCUUCAAACAGUGGUUGGCACUUACCAUGGUUCCCCAGACCAGUCCCAUCAAGUGACUGGUAACCACCAGCAGCCUCCUCAGCAGAACACUGGAUUUCCACGUAGCAAUCAGCCCUAUUACAAUAGUCGUGGUGUGUCUCGUGGAGGCUCCCGUGGUGCUAGAGGCUUGAUGAAUGGAUACCGGGGCCCUGCCAAUGGAUUCAGAGGAGGAUAUGAUGGUUACCGCCCUUCAUUCUCUAACACUCCAAACAGUGGUUAUACACAGUCUCAGUUCAGUGCUCCCCGGGAUUACUCUGGCUAUCAACGGGAUGGAUAUCAGCAGAAUUUCAAGCGAGGCUCUGGGCAGAGUGGACCACGGGGAGCCCCACGAGGUCGUGGAGGGCCCCCAAGACCCAACAGAGGGAUGCCGCAAAUGAACACUCAGCAAGUGAAUUAAUCUGAUUCACAGGAUUAUGUUUAAUCGCCAAAAACACACUGGCCAGUGUACCAUAAUAUGUUACCAGAAGAGUUAUUAUCUAUUUGUUCUCCCUUUCAGGAAACUUAUUGUAAAGGGACUGUUUUCAUCCCAUAAAGACAGGACUACAAUUGUCAGCUUUCUAUUACCUGGAUAUGGAAGGAAACUAUUUUUACUCUGCAUGUUCUGUCCUAAGCGUCAUCUUGAGCCUUGCACAUGAUACUCAGAUUCCUCACCCUUGCUUAGGAGUAAAACAAUAUACUUUACAGGGUGAUAAUAAUCUCCAUAGUUAUUUGAAGUGGCUUGAAAAAGGCAAGAUUGACUUUUAUGACAUUGGAUAAAAUCUACAAAUCAGCCCUCGAGUUAUUCAAUGAUAACUGACAAACUAAAUUAUUUCCCUAGAAAGGAAGAUGAAAGGAGUGGAGUGUGGUUUGGCAGAACAACUGCAUUUCACAGCUUUUCCAGUUAAAUUGGAGCACUGAACGUUCAGAUGCAUACCAAAUUAUGCAUGGGUCCUAAUCACACAUAUAAGGCUGGCUACCAGCUUUGACACAGCACUGUUCAUCUGGCCAAACAACUGUGGUUAAAAACACAUGUAAAAUGCUUUUUAACAGCUGAUACUGUAUAAGACAAAGCCAAGAUGCAAAAUUAGGCUUUGAUUGGCACUUUUUGAAAAAUAUGCAACAAAUAUGGGAUGUAAUCCGGAUGGCCGCUUCUGUACUUAAUGUGAAAUAUUUAGAUACCUUUUUGAACACUUAACAGUUUCUUUGAGACAAUGACUUUUGUAAGGAUUGGUACUAUCUAUCAUUCCUUAUGACAUGUACAUUGUCUGUCACUAAUCCUUGGAUUUUGCUGUAUUGUCACCUAAAUUGGUACAGGUACUGAUGAAAAUCUCUAGUGGAUAAUCAUAACACUCUCGGUCACAUGUUUUUCCUUCAGCUUGAAAGCUUUUUUUUAAAAGGAAAAGAUACCAAAUGCCUGCUGCUACCACCCUUUUCAAUUGCUAUCUUUUGAAAGGCACCAGUAUGUGUUUUAGAUUGAUUUCCCUGUUUCAGGGAAAUCACGGACAGUAGUUUCAGUUCUGAUGGUAUAAGCAAAACAAAUAAAACGUUUAUAAAAGUUGUAUCUUGAAACACUGGUGUUCAACAGCUAGCAGCUUAUGUGAUUCACCCCAUGCCACGUUAGUGUCACAAAUUUUAUGGUUUAUCUCCAGCAACAUUUCUCUAGUACUUGCACUUAUUAUCUUUUGUCUAAUUUAACCUUAACUGAAUUCUCCGUUUCUCCUGGAGGCAUUUAUAUUCAGUGAUAAUUCCUUCCCUUAGAUGCAUAGGGAGAGUCUCUAAAUUUGAUGGAAAUGGACACUUGAGUAGUGACUUAGCCUUAUGUACUCUGUUGGAAUUUGUGCUAGCAGUUUGAGCACUAGUUCUGUGUGCCUAGGAAGUUAAUGCUGCUUAUUGUCUCAUUCUGACUUCAUGGAGAAUUAAUCCCACCUUUAAGCAAAGGCUACUAAGUUAAUGGUAUUUUCUGUGCAGAAAUUAAAUUUUAUUUUCAGCAUUUAGCCCAGGAAUUCUUCCAGUAGGUGCUCAGCUAUUUAAAAACAAAACUAUUCUCAAACAUUCAUCAUUAGACAACUGGAGUUUUUGCUGGUUUUGUAACCUACCAAAAUGGAUAGGCUGUUGAACAUUCCACAUUCAAAAGUUUUGUAGGGUGGUGGGAAAUGGGGGAUCUUCAAUGUUUAUUUUAAAAUAAAAUAAAAUAAGUUCUUGACUUUUCUCAUGUGUGGUUGUGGUACAUCAUAUUGGAAGGGUUAACCUGUUACUUUGGCAAAUGAGUAUUUUUUUGCUAGCACCUCCCCUUGCGUGCUUUAAAUGACAUCUGCCUGGGAUGUACCACAACCAUAUGUUACCUGUAUCUUAGGGGAAUGGAUAAAAUAUUUGUGGUUUACUGGGUAAUCCCUAGAUGAUGUAUGCUUGCAGUCCUAUAUAAAACUAAAUUUGCUAUCUGUGUAGAAAAUAAUUUCAUGACAUUUACAAUCAGGACUGAAGUAAGUUCUUCACACAGUGACCUCUGAAUCAGUUUCAGAGAAGGGAUGGGGGAGAAAAUGCCUUCUAGGUUUUGAACUUCUAUGCAUUAGUGCAGAUGUUGUGAAUGUGUAAAGGUGUUCAUAGUUUGACUGUUUCUAUGUAUGUUUUUUCAAAGAAUUGUUCCUUUUUUUGAACUAUAAUUUUUCUUUUUUUGGUUAUUUUACCAUCACAGUUUAAAUGUAUAUCUUUUAUGUCUCUACUCAGACCAUAUUUUUAAAGGGGUGCCUCAUUAUGGGGCAGAGAACUUUUCAAUAAGUCUCAUUAAGAUCUGAAUCUUGGUUCUAAGCAUUCUGUAUAAUAUGUGAUUGCUUGUCCUAGCUGCAGAAGGCCUUUUGUUUGGUCAAAUGCAUAUUUUAGCAGAGUUUCAAGGAAAUGAUUGUCACACAUGUCACUGUAGCCUCUUGGUGUAGCAAGCUCACAUACAAAAUACUUUUGUAUAUGCAUAAUAUAAAUCAUCUCAUGUGGAUAUGAAACUUCUUUUUUAAAACUUAAAAAGGUAGAAUGUUAUUGAUUACCUUGAUUAGGGCAGUUUUAUUUCCAGAUCCUAAUAAUUCCUAAAAAAUAUGGAAAAGUUUUUUUUCAAUCAUUGUACCUUGAUAUUAAAACAAAUAUCCUUUAAGUAUUUCUAAUCAGUUAGCUUCUACAGUUCUUUUGUCUCCUUUUAUAUGCAGCUCUUACGUGGGAGACUUUUCCACUUAAAGGAGACAUAGAAUGUGUGCUUAUUCUCAGAAGGUUCAUUAACUGAGGUGAUGAGUUAACAACUAGUUGAGCAGUCAGCUUCCUAAGUGUUUUAGGACAUUUGUUCAUUAUAUUUUCCGUCAUAUAACUAGAGGAAGUGGAAUGCAGAUAAGUGCCGAAUUCAAACCCUUCAUUUUAUGUUUAAGCUCCUGAAUCUGCAUUCCACUUGGGUUGUUUUUAAGCAUUCUAAAUUUUAGUUGAUUAUAAGUUAGAUUUCACAGAAUCAGUAUUGCCCUUGAUCUUGUCCUUUUUAUGGAGUUAACGGGGAGGAAGACCCCUCAGGAAAACGAAAGUAAAUUGUUAAGGCUCAUCUUCAUACCUUUUUCCAUUUUGAAUCCUACAAAAAUACUGCAAAAGACUAGUGAAUGUUUAAAAUUACACUAGAUUAAAUAAUAUGAAAGUC